UUUUUGUUUUUUUUUUUUUUUUUGUAUUUUUAGUAGAGACAGGGUUUCACUGUAUUAGCCAGGAUGGUCUAGAUCUCCUGACCUCAUGAUCCGCCCGCCUCGGCCUCCCAACGUGCUGGGAUUACAGGCGUGAGCCACUGCGCCCGGCCAGGCAAAUGAUAUUUUAAGACAUAUAUCUGUUGUCUUUUGUCCCUUUGUGGUGAUCAAGAAAUUGAUGAACCAGAGUUAUUUUAAAAUAUUUUCUAUUGCUGAGCUGUGUCAUUUUGGCUGCAAUAUUUCAUAGAGGCCAAACCACAUAUGAGCUACCACAUUAACAGGGUUAUAUAUUAGUAGGAUUGAAUUUGUGAGGUAAAUCCUGAAGAUCAAAUAAUCUCAACUUUGAAUGGAACUUUAGACAUCACCUAGGUCAACUGCUCAGACAUUGCUUCUCAAAGUGUGGUCCCUGGACCAGCAGCAUCUGCAUUCCCUAAGAACUUGUUAGAAAUCAGAUUCUCAAGCCUCACCCCAAAUCUACUUAGUCGGAAUCUGUGGAAUGGGGCUAACGAAACUGAGUCAGAUUGCUAAUACAGUUCUCAAACAGAGCAUAGAUAGGAGGAGGGCUUCUUAAAACACAGUUGCCUGAGCCCCACCCCCAGAGAUUCUGAUUCACAAGGUCAUCAGUGGGUUCUAUGAAUCUGUGUUUUUAACACGCUCAUAAAUAAUGCCAUACUGCUGGCCCAGGGACAUACAGUACUUCAAAAACCAACCCUCUGAGUAAUACCAGAAUCUUUCCUGCAACAACCUUUGUAGUUGAUCAUUUGGCUUCUGUUUCUUACAUCUAAGGUCCAGGAGCCCACCACUUCAUAAAGCAAGCCUUUUUAAUAUUGAGCAGCUGCAUUAGCUUUCCCUGAGAGUGAAGUCAAAGCUUGCCUCAUUAUUCUUGCCACCCAUCACUCAUGAUGCUCUCAUGGCCACUUGCAGUACCAAUGUUCGUAGGCUGAUUCCAGGUGUAGCCUUAAUUGUCAGGUGGCUCUUACCCACUUGUAAUCACCAUUGAACCCUUCUCCUUCAGCUACUGAAGCAGGAGUAGUAACUCAUCAACAUCCCUUCUUUUUGUCUUUUUAAAAGACAGAUUCUCACUCUGUUGCCCAGGCUGGAGUACAGUGGCAUGAUCAUAGCCCACUGCAGCCUUGAACUCCUGGGCUCGAUGAUCCUCCUGCCUCAGCCUCCUGAGUAGCUAGGACUACAGUGAGGGUGAAAAUCUCACUGGACUGGCUUCAAGAGAUAAUGAGAGGAGAUGAUUGGAAACAACGACUACAGUCAACUCUUUGCACAGGUGGAGGGAAUGACAGCUGCCCAGCCUCCAGGCCCACUGAUGGACCCGUUAACGAAGGUGCCUUGUGGGAGUCAGAUAGCACAAACCAUUCUAUGGAAAGCAAAGUCGUCUCUCUCCUUCGGCAUCCAGCCCCUUCAGACAUGGCCAACGAAAGACCCUGAACUAGAGUCCCAGGUCAACCUCUCUGUCUCGGAAGACCUAGGCUGUAGACGUGGGGAUUUCAGUAGGAAACAUUAUGGAUCUGUGGAGCUGCUUAUUUCCAGUGAUGCUGAUGGAGCCAUCCAAAGGGCUGGAAGAUUCAGAGUGGAAAAUGGCUCUUCAGAUGAGAAUGCAACUGCCCUGCCUGGUACUUGGCGAAGAACAGACGUGCACUUAGAGAACCCAGAAUACCACACCAGAUGGUAUUUCAAAUAUUUUUUAGGACAAGUCCAUCAGAACUACAUUGGAAACGAUGCCGAGAAGAGCCCUUUCUUCUUGUCCGUGACCCUUUCUGACCAAAACAAUCAACGUGUCCCUCAAUACCGUGCAAUUCUUUGGAGAAAAACAGGUACCCAGAAAAUAUGCCUUCCCUACAGUCCCACAAAAACUCUUUCUGUGAAGUCCAUCUUAAGUGCCAUGAAUCUGGACAAAUUUGAGAAAGGCCCCAGGGAAAUUUUUCAUCCUGAAAUACAAAAGGACUUGCUGGUUCUUGAAGAACAAGAGGGCUCUGUGAAUUUCAAGUUUGGGGUUCUUUUUGCCAAAGAUGGGCAGCUCACUGAUGAUGAGAUGUUCAGCAAUGAAAUUGGAAGCGAGCCUUUUCAAAAAUUUUUAAAUCUUCUGGGUGACACAAUCACUCUAAAGGGCUGGACGGGCUACCGUGGCGGUCUGGAUACCAAAAAUGAUACCACAGGGAUACAUUCAGUUUAUACUGUGUACCAAGGGCAUGAGAUCAUGUUUCAUGUUUCCACCAUGUUGCCAUAUUCCAAAGAGAACAAACAGCAGGUGGAAAGGAAACGCCACAUUGGAAACGAUAUCGUCACCAUUGUGUUCCAAGAAGGAGAGGAAUCUUCUCCUGCCUUUAAGCCUUCCAUGAUCCGCUCCCACUUUACACAUAUUUUUGCCUUAGUGAGAUACAAUCAACAAAAUGACAAUUACAGGCUGAAAAUAUUUUCAGAAGAGAGCGUACCACUCUUUGGCCCUCCCUUGCCAACUCCACCAGUGUUUACAGACCACCAGGAAUUCAGGGACUUUUUGCUAGUGAAAUUAAUUAAUGGUGAAAAAGCCACUUUGGAAACCCCAACAUUUGCCCAGAAACGUCGGCGUACCCUGGAUAUGUUGAUUAGAUCUUUACACCAGGAUUUGAUGCCAGAUUUGCAUAAGAACAUGCUUAAUAGACGAUCUUUUAGUGAUGUCUUACCAGAGUCACCCAAGUCAGCGCGGAAGAAAGAGGAGGCCCGCCAGGCGGAGUUUGUUAGAAUAGGGCAGGCACUAAAACUGAAAUCCAUUGUGAGAGGGGAUGCUCCAUCAAGCUUGGCAGCUUCAGGGAUCUGUAAAAAAGAGCCGUGGGAGCCCCAGUGUUUCUGCAGUAAUUUCCCUCAUGAAGCCGUGUGUGCAGAUCCCUGGGGCCAGGCCUUGCUGGUUUCCACUGAUGCUGGCGUCUUGCUAGUGGAUGAUGACCUUCCAUCAGUGCCCGUGUUUGACAGAACUCUGCCAGUGAAGCAAAUGCAUGUGCUUGAGACCCUGGACCUUCUGGUUCUCAGAGCAGACAAAGGAAAAGAUGCUCGCCUCUUUGUCUUCAGGCUAAGUGCUCUGCAAAAGGGCCUUGAGGGGAAGCAGGCUGGGAAGAGCAGGUCUGACUGCAGAGAAAACAAGUUGGAGAAAACAAAAGGCUGCCACCUGUAUGCUAUUAACACUCACCACAGCAGAGAGCUGAGGAUUGUGGUUGCAAUUCGGAAUAAACUGCUUCUGAUCACAAGAAAACACAACAAGCCAAGCGGGGUCACCAGCACCUCAUUGUUAUCUCCCCUGUCUGAGUCACCUGUUGAAGAAUUCCAGUACAUCAGGGAGAUCUGUCUGUCUGACUCUCCCAUGGUGAUGACCUUAGUGGAUGGGCCAGCUGAAGAGAGUGACAAUCUCAUCUGUGUGGCUUAUCGACACCAAUUUGAUGUGGUGAAUGAGAGCACAGGAGAAGCCUUCAGGCUGCACCACGUGGAGGCCAACAGGGUUAAUUUUGUUGCAGCUAUUGAUGUGUACGAAGAUGGAGAAGCUGGUUUGCUGUUGUGUUACAACUACAGUUGCAUCUAUAAAAAGGUUUGCCCCUUUAAUGGUGGCUCUUUUUUGGUUCAACCUUCUGCGUCAGAUUUCCAGUUCUGUUGGAACCAGGCUCCCUAUGCAAUUGUCUGUGCUUUCCCGUAUCUCCUGGCCUUCACCACCGACUCCAUGGAGAUCCGCCUGGUGGUGAACGGGAACCUGGUCCACACUGCAGUCGUGCCGCAGCUGCAGCUGGUGGCCUCCAGGUCGGAUAUAUACUUCACAGCAACUGCAGCUGUGAAUGAGGUCUCAUCUGGAGGCAGCUCCAAGGGGGCCAGUGCCCGAAAUUCUCCUCAGACACCCCCGGGCCGAGAUACUCCAGUAUUUCCUUCUUCCCUGGGGGAAGGUGAAAUUCAAUCAAAAAAUCUGUACAAGAUUCCACUUAGAAACCUCGUGGGCAGAAGCAUCGAACGACCUCUGAAGUCACCCUUAGUCUCCAAGGUCAUCACCCCACCCACUCCCAUCAGUGUGGGCCUUGCUGCCAUUCCAGUCACGCACUCCUUGUCCCUGUCUCGCAUGGAGAUCAAAGAAAUAGCAAGCAGGACCCGCAGGGAACUACUGGGCCUCUCGGAUGAAGGUGGACCCAAGUCAGAAGGAGCGCCAAAGGCCAAAUCAAAACCCCGGAAGCGGUUAGAAGAAAGCCAAGGAGGCCCCAAGCCAGGGGCAGUGAGGUCAUCUAGCAGUGACAGGAUCCCAUCAGGCUCCUUGGAAAGUGCUUCUACUUCCGAAGCCAACCCUGAGGGGCACUCAGCCAGCUCUGACCAGGACCCUGUGGCAGACAGAGAGGGCAGCCCGGUCUCCGGCAGCAGCCCCUUCCAGCUCACGGCUUUCUCCGAUGAAGACAUUAUAGACUUGAAGUAACAGAGUUGAAUCUCAUUUGCCAUCUUUAGUUUUCUUAUGGAGGUUUAUACUCUUUAAACAGUUCUGAUGUAAUUUCUCAACAAAAUGUGGCUUUUAGCCUGUCAGUGAUCUAUUGGACCAAACCUUCUGCACACUCGGCCAGUUCCCUCUCCAAUGUCCGGUGCCAUCUUUCCUGACCUUUGUUUCUUUCUGUUCAGGAACCAUCAGUCCCCUUGUAAUAAAGGUGGUAGAUUUCAUUGAGGUUUUAGAUUGAAACUUUGAAUAAAUCAAAAAUACUCAUUCUUAUUUACUGCAACCUUCUCAUAUUUUAUAUACUUAGAUGGAAAAUUAUUUUUUCAUUACAGUUUUGAUUUAUGUCACAUAAUGUGUUUCUUUUAUAAAGAAAAGUCGUUGCUUUUUAACUUUA